ACUUUCGUCUUAGCUUUUGGACAAGACGCAGGCGCAACCCACGGCUGCUGCGGGGAUCCUUGUGGCCCUUCCGGUCGGUGGAACCAAUCCGUGCACAGAGAAGCGGGGCGAACUGAGGCGAGUGAAGUGGACUCUGAGGGCUACCGCUACCGCCACUGCUGCGGCAGGGGCGUGGAGGGCAGAGGGCCGCGGAGGCCGCAGUUGCAAACAUGGCUCAGAGCAGAGACGGCGGAAACCCGUUCGCCGAGCCCAGCGAGCUUGACAACCCCUUUCAGGACCCAGCUGUGAUCCAGCACCGACCCAGCCGGCAGUAUGCCACGCUUGACGUCUACAACCCUUUUGAGACCCGGGAGCCACCACCAGCCUAUGAGCCUCCAGCCCCUGCCCCAUUGCCUCCACCCUCAGCUCCCUCCUUGCAGCCCUCGAGAAAGCUCAGCCCCACAGAACCUAAGAACUAUGGCUCAUACAGCACUCAGGCCUCAGCUGCAGCAGCCACAGCUGAGCUGCUGAAGAAACAGGAGGAGCUCAACCGGAAGGCAGAGGAGUUGGACCGAAGGGAGCGAGAGCUGCAGCAUGCUGCCCUGGGGGGCACAGCUACUCGACAGAACAAUUGGCCCCCUCUACCUUCUUUUUGUCCAGUUCAGCCCUGCUUUUUCCAGGACAUCUCCAUGGAGAUCCCCCAAGAAUUUCAGAAGACUGUAUCCACCAUGUACUACCUCUGGAUGUGCAGCACGCUGGCUCUUCUCCUGAACUUCCUCGCCUGCCUGGCCAGCUUCUGUGUGGAAACCAACAAUGGCGCAGGCUUUGGGCUUUCUAUCCUCUGGGUCCUCCUUUUCACUCCCUGCUCCUUUGUCUGCUGGUACCGCCCCAUGUAUAAGGCUUUCCGGAGUGACAGUUCAUUCAAUUUCUUCGUUUUCUUCUUCAUUUUCUUCGUCCAGGAUGUGCUCUUUGUCCUCCAGGCCAUUGGUAUCCCAGGUUGGGGAUUCAGUGGCUGGAUCUCUGCUCUGGUGGUGCCGAAGGGCAACACAGCAGUAUCCGUGCUCAUGCUGCUGGUCGCCCUGCUCUUCACUGGCAUUGCUGUGCUAGGAAUUGUCAUGCUGAAACGGAUCCACUCCUUAUACCGCCGCACAGGUGCCAGCUUUCAGAAGGCCCAGCAAGAAUUUGCUGCUGGUGUCUUCUCCAACCCUGCGGUGCGAACCGCAGCUGCCAAUGCAGCCGCUGGGGCUGCUGAAAAUGCCUUCCGGGCCCCGUGACCCCUGACUGGGAUGCCCUGGCCCUGCUACUUGAGGGAGCUGACUUAGCUCCCGUCCCUAAGGUCUCUGGGACUUGGAGAGACAUCACUAACUGAUGGCUCCUCCGUAGUGCUCCCAAUCCUAUGGCCAUGACUGCUGAACCUGACAGGCGUGUGGGGAGUUCACUGUGACCUAGUCCCCCCAUCAGGCCACACUGCUGCCACCUCUCACACGCCCCAACCCAGCUUCCCUCUGCUGUGCCACGGCUGUUGCUUCGGUUAUUUAAAUAAAAAGAAAGUGGAACUGGAACUGA